AUGCCGUCCUUGAGGCUCUCACACAUGCACACAGACGCUCCGUCCUCUCCCACCCGCCCCCCCGCCACCCCGGGCAGGCCAGGAAGUCCCAUCUGGGGCCUCCCACCCCGAGGGUUGCCGUCAGUCCGUGUGCCCAGGCAUCGGGGCCUGCAGCCUCCACAGACAGCGAGACCUGUGUGCGAAGCAGACUCUGUCCUAGGGACAGUGCUGACCCUACAAGGCUGGGUCACUGGAGGCUCCCCGGGUCCAGUGGCUUUGGUGGGACUCCUGGCCAGGCUCCUCCUGGGCCGGGCUGGUCUCCGGCCUCCUGCCUCCCUUGGUGGAGCACCCUUGCUCCCCAGCACCUCCCAGGUUCACACAGCUCCUCCCUGGGGCUGCGCACUGACCCAGGGGCAGGAGGUGGGCCAUCCUCUCGGUGGACUGAAGACCUUGUCCGAAGGGAAAGCAGGGCCGGCCCAAGGCCUGGCUGGAAGAGUGGGUCUUGGUGGCAAAGGCGGCCCGUGGGGGGAGCCCACGCGAAUGCUUCCCCGGCGCCCUGAGCCCCUGACCGCGGCUGAGCCUGCGGGAACAGCUUCCGGCUGCCUGCACUGUUUGGGCGCCGUCAUAAGGAGCCGUGACGGCCUUCACGGAGCUCCGGGGCUCACGGGUGUGGCUGACCUGCCACAAAUGGGGCGACAGAGGAGAGGGAGGGUCGGGCACCGAUGGCUCAGGAGGGAAGAGAUCCCUUCUGUAUGGGGAGACGGGGGCUUCCUGGAGGGCACUGGAGCGAGGGGCUCACCAGAAACUAAAAGGCAAACGAAAUCCCUGCUCCAUCACUGCCUGUCCCGGGUCGCGGCGCGGGACAUUUCCUCCAAGCGCCUUCCCGGCCCCGCGCGCAGGUGGCCUGCGCCGGAGGAUCCCGGACAACGCGCAUUUCCUGCGCCCCCGGAAGCGGCGGUAACGCCUGGCCCUGCCCCCGGCAGAGGCGGAAGCACAGUCGCUCUGAGGUCGCCCGUGGCCGCAGGUGCCUCAGCCCAGCCGCGCGCCUUGGCCCUUGGCCGCCUACUCCUACCGCCCCGGCCUUGGGCGGCCCUGGGCCUGCUGCGGGCGCGGCGCUGCCCGACCAGAGCUUCCUGUGGAACGUCUUCCAGAGCUGCCACCUGGCACCGCCCCGGCACCUCCCGCCUCCCCCGCAGCUGCCCCGGACCCGUGUCCCGACCCCCGCGGCCAACCCCGUUCCCUGCCGGUUGCCCCGCGGCCUCCCCCGUCACCUGCCGGGUCCCCAGCGGCCUCCCCCGUCCCCUGCCCCGACCUCCGCCGUCUCCCCCGCCCCUGCCCGGACCCCCGCGGGCGCCCCCGAACCCUACCCCGACCGACGCGGCCGCCCCCAUCCCCUGCCCCGACCCCCGCGGCCGCCCCCAUCCCCUUCCGGGUCCCCCGCGGUCUCCCCCGUCCGCUGCCCGGUCUCCUGGGGCCGCCCCUGCCUCCUGCCCGGUCCCUGUCCUGUGCGUCGGGCCCUUCCCAAGGUGCAGAGGGCGCCACUGCAGACCCGAGGUCGCGGCCACCGGCUCCUGGGCCAGGCCCUGUUUCUCGCCUCGAGCCGUCGGGGGAGGGUCUCCAGGGUGCUUGUUUGGGGAAAGCGGAAACAGACUGUCUGGGCCGCUGUUAAAAUGUCAGCAGCCAAGGAAGAAGCAGCGACCUGGCGUCUGCUCGGGCCAGGAUGAAGCCCCACCCGCUGUACAGGAUGCAAAGCCCUCCUCUAUAAAGUGCGUGCGGGGCCAGAUGCAGUGGCUCACGUCUGACCUCCCAACACUUUGGGAGGCCGAGGCAGGGGCAUCGUUUGAGACCAGCCUGGACAACAUUGUGAGACCCUGUUCCUUGAAUUGCCCUGGGAGAUUUCCUCAGCUUGUACUGGAGGAUGAAGCCCCACCCGCCCUUCAGGAUGCCAGCCUUGGCAACAUUGUGAAACCGCACUGAGAAGGUAUUUGUGGCCCGUAUGCUGAUUGAUUGAUGAGACUUCUUUGCACAGGAGAGCUGCUAAAAAUUACUGCGGUGAACAGUCUUGUUCCAGUGGUUCAUCGGUGACUUCUGUGGCUUCGUCAUCAUUAUCCAUGGAUGAUUCUGAAAGAAUCUCUCCAGUUUUACUGGAAUUGGAUCCUACUAAUUCUUCUGUUUCACGGCAGUCAGAAGAACCACUACUUUCAGGGCCUUCGUUUUCACUACCUUCAGAAUGUAGUAAAUCUUUCUCAGCUUGAGACACAUCAGAUUCCUCCAUUUCAUUAUUUUCCUCAGAAGUCUCUUCAUUCACAGUUGAGGCAUCAUCAGAUUCUUUUUCUUGGUUUUUUCUUUCUGGGACCAUUUCUCUUGAUGUCAUAAAAGACUCUAAAAAUAAGCAAAUGUUGUUGUACUUAAAUUUUAUAUUCAAAAUACCUCCACAGUUAAGUUUUGUGAAUUCUGAUGUUCUGUAGUUCAAAUCACAUCCCCUGAAAUUCAGCAGCAACUGCAUACAGGUGGGAGAAAAGCCCAGCGUCGACAUUACAAGGAGUUCCAUGAUGUACAAUUCUUUCACGAAAACAAUGAAUGCAAGAAUUUGAGGAUCUCCUUACUCCUCCCUUUUACAGAUGGUCUCUCAAUCCCUUCUUCUUCCUCUUCAUCUUCAUCUUCUUCUGAACGCGCUGCCGGGUACCACGGCUUUCUUUGUCUUUAUCGUGAGAUGAAGGUGAUGCUUCUGUUUCUUCUACCAUAACUGAAGAAAUUUCGCUGCAAGUCUCUUGACUGGCUGUUUCUCCGACUUCGCCUUUUUGUCAAACGUGAGUCUUUUUACCUCAUGCCCCUCAGCUUCCACAGCAUCUUCAUCUGGAUGUUUAUUUCUCAAAGGGCUCACUGAGGAAACUUCUGAUUCAGAUGUCGAAGAGUCACUGUGAGUUUUCUCUUCAUUUUGCUGCAAAUUUGCCUCUUUGCUGUCUGUGCUCUCAGGCCACCCAUUUGUUGUCAUGGGGGCUGACAGAGAAACCUUUGGUCGAUUACGUGGCCUGGGUGUCCCAGGCCCAUUUAUAUUAGACCUCUCAGUAUAGCUUGGUGCAUUUCCAGGAAACAUCACACCAUUCAUUCGAUUUAAACUAUUGGAAUUGUUUUUCUCUGAAGAAGGAUAAACACAGCUAACAACCAUCACGUUCUUUUCUACUCCUCUGAGAAAUUUGUCUGUUCCUGUAUAGUUUCUCCUUGGAUCUGUUAACAAUUCACAUAGUCGCUGAAUAGUAAAAGGGAUACGGUUAAAUCCAGUGACAGUUUUCAGUAUUCUUCCCUUUGUUUCAUCAAAGGGAAUAUAUUCGACUUUAGGGUUGGGAGGACCUCUUGGCGCAGGAGCUGAAGUUCUGAAAUCAUCUAUCACUUUCUCCAGUUUGAAAAUAAAAUAGCCUUUAAAUUGGGACCACUGAAUCUGUUUCUCCAGUCUUGGCUACAUGACAAAGGAACUGAUCCAGGACAGGACAGACUUUCUUUUUUGCCUCUUCUCAAAAUCUUCCAGCGCCUCCUGGAGCCUGUCGACGUCCAUGGCUUCCCAGAGUCCCUCACAGCCUCCGUCUCCCUCCGCGGGUCUCUUGGGGACCGGAACGCCUCCCCCCACCCCCCGACAUCCUCCCACUCCCUCGCACACCCUCCAGCACGCAGGCCAAGUGGGGUGGGGGGGAACGAAGGGAGCCAGGGGAAGCGUGUGAGAGAGUGAGACCGACAGAGUGAGCACCUCCCCAAGCCGCUACCACCAGCCCUCCAACAUGGCGCCUGGCACAUCACCCUAAAAAGUCAUUUCUUGGAGAAGCGAUGGAUGACAGAGAUUAAUCUGAGAGUUACUAUUAAUGGAGAAACUUAGAACUUACCAUUUUUCCUGUGAGGUUUCGGUGCUGAUACUUCUAUUCUGUGAGUUCUGGCAAUUGUGUCCGUUCACCCAGCCUGGUGAUGCAGCAGGUGUCACAGAAGGACCCUGUCCCAGCUGGUCCUGCUCCACUGCUAGGAUGGUGUGGCCUCUGAUCUGUGACCGUGUCUUGAGGGGAGACCAGGCCCUUGAUCACAAGCGUAUCCAUGGUGAGGUUCCGUGGAUGGAAGCUCAUGGAUGUUCCUUCCUGAUGUUCAUCUGCCACCAUGCUAUUGAAUGCAUCUUGUUUAUAACUGUCUUCUAAAUAUUGAAUAGAAAUAAAGCAUUUGUACAGUAUGGUUAAGGUAUAAAGAAUAUUGACACAUUGGACACAGAGGACCUCCACCAAGUUUAGGGAGUAGAAUCUGAAGAGACAUAGCUUUGGAUGCUCCCUGGAGGCCCUGCCUGAGUCCCAGUCCCUUCCCUUCUCCUACGGAGGGAAUCAUUUCCUGCUUUAGUCUUUAUUAUUUGCACACUUUCCUUCAUAGUAUGUUUCUUUCACCGUGUGUGUACAUCCCUAAAAGAUAUGCCAUUUAGUUUUUGAACUUUCUGUUUUCUUUUUGAGGCAGGGUCUUGCUCUGUUGCCUCGGCUGUAGUUUUGAACUUUGACGUGAGGGAAUUCUCCUGCGUGGCUGCUCCUGCACUGCAUGGCUCUGAGCACCUGCUCUGUGUCUAUUUUUGUCCUCCAUUCUCUCCCUGAGACCCACCCACACUGACAUGGCUCAUUUUCAUUGCUGCAUGGUCUCCCGUCGUCUGAGGGGAGCAUGGGAAAUGUCUUCAUCUUCCCGUGGAUGAGUGUUUGGCCAGGUUGGGGCCCUUAGGACUGUGUUUUGUUGGGAACGUUCUUGGGCAUUUCUUUUGUACACAGCGCAAGUUUCUUCUGGUCAGUAGCUUUCAAAUUUUAAAAUUUCAUCCCAGGUAAAAAUGUAAUUUUCCUCAUAACCCACAACACACACUCUUUCAUAUACAAGCAUAGCAGAAAUAUACUUCACAAGCGUUAGCAGUGCCUGUUGUUCCUGCUUCUCUCCAUUCUCCCCAACGCUGGCAUGGAUUGGGUUGUGGGAUUUUUGCCCGUCUGGUGGUUGUCACGUGAUAUCUCCCCCUGUUAGGCUGAGCCCCUCUUCAUGUUUUCAUUAGCCAUUCCUCCACAUUUCCUCUUCUGUGGAGGGCCGGUUCAGCUCUUUUGCCCAGUUUCUGUUAAGUUGUUUGAAUUUUUGCACUUUUCCUUUAUUAUUCCUAUUACUAUGUUUUUGAGACAGAAUAUCACUCUGUCACCCAGGCUGGAUGUGAUCUCAGCUCACUGCAACCUCCAUCUUCUGGGUUCAAAUGAUUCUCCUGCCUCAGCCUCCCAAGUGGCUGGGAUUACAGGCACACACCACCAUGCCCAGCUAAUUUUUAUAUGUUUACUACAGAUGGGUUUUCACUAUGUUGUCCAGGCUGGUCUGAAACUCCUGACCUCAGGUGAUUCUCCCACCUCAGCCUCCCAAAGUGCUGGGAUUAUGUGGGUGGCAAGCCACCCAGGCACCGAGGCAAGAGACAGAGGACACGAGCUGUUCCAGUAUAAUAAAAUAUAAAACAAGAAUAGUUAUGCCAGAUAUAGAUCUUAGAUAUGAUUAUAUAUGAAUAUCAUUAAUCAUUAGUUUGUAGCAAUUGCUUUUUAUUCCAAUAUUAUGAUAAUCCUCGCUCUAUAAUCAUAGUGUAGGAAAAACCAGGCCAUACAGAGAUAGGAGCUGAGGGGACAUAGUGAGGUGUGACCAGAAGACAAGAGUGCGAGCCUUCUGUUAUGCCCGGACCGGGCCACCAGAGGGCUCCUUGGUCUAGCGGUGAUGCCAGCGUCUGGGAAGAUGCCUGUUACCAGGCGGAUCGUGGUCCAGCAGUAGCAAAAGGUGUCAAGGAACAACACCCGAUACUUAGCAGACCAGGAAAGGGCGGGGGGGGGGGGGGUCUCCCUUUCCCCGGGGGAGUUUAGAGAAGACUCUGCUCCUCCACCUCUUGUGGAGGGCCUGACAUCAGUCAGGCUCGCCUGCAGUUAUCCGGAGGCCUAACCGUCUCCCUGUGAUGCUGUGCUUCAGUGGUCACGCUCCUAGUCCGCCUUCAUGUUUCAUCCUGUACACCUGGCUCUGCCUUCUAGAUAGCAGUAGUAAAUUAGUAAAAAUACUAAUAGUCCCUGAUAUGCGGAAAUAAUGGCAUAAGCUGUCUUUCUCUCUGUCUCCUCUCCCUCUCUGCCUCGGCUGCCAGGCAGGGAAGGGCCCCCUGUCCAGUGGACACGUGACCCACGUGACCUUACCUAUCAUUGGAGGUGACUCACAUUCUUUACCCUGCCCCUUCUGCCUUGUAUCCAAUAAAUAACAGCGCAGCCAGACAUUCGGGGCACUACUGUUCUCCGCGCAUUGGUGGUAGUGGUCCCCCAGGCCCAGCUGCCCUUUCUCUUA